GAGCAGUGGCCGUUACGGCCGAAAAGAUGGCGGUCUUGGCACCUCUAAUUGCUCUCGUGUAUUCGGUGCCGCGACUUUCACGAUGGCUCGCCCAACCUUACUACCUUCUGUCGGCCCUGCUCUCUGCUGCCUUCCUACUCGUGAGGAAACUGCCGCCGCUCUGCCACGGUCUGCCCACCCAACGCGAAGACGGUAACCCGUGUGACUUUGACUGGAGAGAAGUGGAGAUCCUGAUGUUUCUCAGUGCCAUUGUGAUGAUGAAGAACCGCAGAUCCAGCUGAAUUUGAACUUGGACUUCUAUCCCCUCCCUGUCUCCUAUUUCAAAGUGCCCCAUGAAGAGGGACAAAGAAUGGGAUAUAGGAGUGCACAGCCCAGCCUGACCUGUGACAUCUCUGUGUUUCAGUCACUGUGGAGCAACAUAUAGGCAACAUUUUCAUGUUUAGUAAAGUGGCCAACACAAUUCUUUUCUUCCGCUUGGAUAUUCGCAUGGGCCUACUUUACAUCACACUCUGCAUAGUGUUCCUGAUGACGUGCAAACCCCCCCUAUAUAUGGGCCCUGAGUAUAUCAAGUACUUCAAUGAUAAAACCAUUGAUGAGGAACUAGAACGGGACAAGAGGGUCACUUGGAUUGUGGAGUUCUUUGCCAAUUGGUCUAAUGACUGCCAAUCAUUUGCCCCUAUCUAUGCUGACCUCUCCCUUAAAUACAACUGUACAGGGCUAAAUUUUGGGAAGGUGGAUGUUGGACGCUAUACUGAUGUUAGUACGCGGUACAAAGUGAGCACAUCACCCCUCACCAAGCAACUCCCUACCCUGAUCCUGUUCCAAGGUGGCAAGGAGGCAAUGCGGCGGCCACAGAUUGACAAGAAAGGACGGGCUGUCUCAUGGACCUUCUCUGAGGAGAAUGUGAUCCGAGAAUUUAACUUAAAUGAGCUAUACCAGCGGGCCAAGAAACUAUCAAAGGCUGGAGACAAUAUCCCUGAGGAGCAGCCUGUGGCUUCAACCCCCACCACAGUGUCAGAUGGGGAAAACAAGAAGGAUAAAUAAGAUCCUCACUUUGGCAGUGCUUCCUCUCCUGUCAAUUCCAGGCUCUUUCCAUAACCACAAGCCUGAGGCUGCAGCCUUUUAUUUAUGUUUUCCCUUUGGCUGUGACUGGGUGGGGCAGCAUGCAGCUUCUGAUUUUAAAGAGGCAUCUAGGGAAUUGUCAGGCACCCUACAGGAAGGCCUGCCAUGCUGUGGCCAACUGUUUCACUGGAGCAAGAAAGAGAUCUCAUAGGACGGAGGGGGAAAUGGUUUCCCUCCAAGCUUGGGUCAGUGUGUUAACUGCUUAUCAGCUAUUCAGACAUCUCCAUGGUUUCUCCAUGAAACUCUGUGGUUUCAUCAUUCCUUCUUAGUUGACCUGCACAGCUUGGUUAGACCUAGAUUUAACCCUAAGGUAAGAUGCUGGGGUAUAGAACGCUAAGAAUUUUCCCCCAAGGACUCUUGCUUCCUUAAGCCCUUCUGGCUUCGUUUAUGGUCUUCAUUAAAAGUAUAAGCCUAACUUUGUCGCUAGUCCUAAGGAGAAACCUUUAACCACAAAGUUUUUAUCAUUGAAGACAAUAUUGAACAACCCCCUAUUUUGUGGGGAUUGAGAAGGGGUGAAUAGAGGCUUGAGACUUUCCUUUGUGUGGUAGGACUUGGAGGAGAAAUCCCCUGGACUUUCACUAACCCUCUGACAUACUCCCCACACCCAGUUGAUGGCUUUCCGUAAUAAAAAGAUUGGGAUUUCCUUUUGA